AUUUGGAGUCAGGCCUGGCUGUUGCUCAGGUGACCAGCUUGUGUCUCUGGGAGGGCGCUGCUUUCCCCGGCCACCCGGCGCGAUGAUCCAGAAUGUCGGAAAUCACCUGCGACGGGGCUUGGCCUCUGUGUUCUCCAACCGCACAUCCCGGAAGUCAGCCUUACGUGCGGGGAACGACAGUGCCAUGGCAGACGGCGAGGGAUACCGGAACCCCACGGAGGUGCAGAUGAGCCAGCUGGUGCUGCCCUGCCACACCAACCAACGUGGUGAGCUGAGCGUCGGGCAGCUGCUCAAGUGGAUUGACACCACGGCUUGCCUGUCCGCGGAGAGGCACGCUGGCUGCCCCUGUGUCACAGCUUCCAUGGAUGACAUCUAUUUUGAGCACACCAUUAGUGUUGGACAAGUGGUGAAUAUCAAGGCCAAGGUGAACCGGGCCUUCAACUCCAGCAUGGAGGUGGGCAUCCAGGUGGCCUCGGAGGACCUGUGCUCUGAGAAGCAGUGGAAUGUGUGCAAGGCCUUGGCCACCUUCGUGGCCCGCCGAGAGAUCACCAAGGUGAAGCUGAAGCAGAUCACGCCGCGGACAGAAGAGGAGAAGAUGGAGCACAGUGUGGCGGCUGAGCGCCGGCGCAUGCGCCUUGUCUAUGCAGACACCAUCAAGGACCUCCUGGCCAACUGCGCCAUUCAGGGCGAUCUGGAGAGCAGAGACUGUAGCCGCAUGGUGCCGGCUGAGAAGACCCGUGUGGAGAGUGUGGAGCUGGUCCUGCCUCCCCACGCCAAUCACCAGGGCAACACCUUUGGGGGCCAGAUCAUGGCCUGGAUGGAGAAUGUGGCCACCAUUGCAGCCAGCCGGCUCUGCCGUGCCCACCCUACGCUGAAGGCCAUUGAAAUGUUCCACUUCCGAGGCCCGUCCCAGGUCGGCGACCGUCUGGUGCUCAAAGCCAUCGUGAACAAUGCCUUCAAACAUAGCAUGGAGGUGGGCGUGUGCGUGGAGGCCUAUCGCCAGGAGGCUGAGACCCACCGGCGCCACAUCAACAGUGCCUUUAUGACCUUUGUGGUCCUGGACGCAGAUGACCAGCCCCAGUUGCUGCCCUGGAUUCGGCCCCAGCCCGGCGAUGGUGAGCGGCGGUACCGAGAGGCCAGUGCCAGAAAGAAGAUCCGCCUGGACAGGAAGUACAUCGUGUCCUGUAAGCAGACAGAGGUGCCCCUCUCCGUCCCCUGGGACCCUAGCAACCAGGUGUACCUGAGCUACAAUAACGUCUCCUCCUUGAAGAUGCUUGUGGCCAAGGACAACUGGGUGCUGUCCUCGGAGAUCAGUCAGGUCCGCCUGUACACUCUGGAGGAUGACAAGUUCCUCUCCUUCCACAUGGAGAUGGUGGUGCAUGUGGAUGCAGCCCAGGCCUUCCUGCUGCUCUCGGACCUGCGUCAGAGGCCAGAGUGGGACAAGCACUACCGGAGCGUGGAGCUAGUGCAGCAGGUAGACGAGGACGACGCCAUCUACCACGUCACCAGCCCUGCCCUCGGAGGUCACACAAAGCCCCAGGACUUCGUGAUCCUGGCCUCGAGGCGGAAGCCUUGUGACAAUGGGGACCCCUAUGUCAUCGCGCUGAGGUCGGUCACGCUGCCCACACACCGAGAGACGCCAGAGUACAGACGCGGAGAGACCCUCUGCUCAGGCUUCUGCCUCUGGCGCGAGGGGGACCAGCUGACCAAGUGCUGCUGGGUUAGGGUCUCCCUGACUGAGCUGGUCUCGGCAAGUGGCUUCUAUUCCUGGGGGCUCGAAUCCAGGUCAAAGGGUCGCAGGAGCGACGGUUGGAAUGGAAAACUAGCUGGAGGACACCUGAGUACUCUUAAAGCAAUCCCCGUGGCCAAAAUCAACAGCCGAUUUGGAUACCUUCAAGACACCUGAAACCUUAUCAUGAGCCAGAUGCCAAGGAAGAGACUCUGGGAGGAUCCAGAGGACCCCCUGGUUGCAGCCACGUAGAGACUGACGCUGAGGAGGACUCCAACUAUCAUGAGCAACACCCGUCGAACACAGCCACCCCGCUAAGAACAGAUCAAGAAGCUGUCACAGAUGGCGGAAGAAAACCUGAGGAAAGCGGGACAACCAGUCACAAUGAAUAAUUUAAUGGUAGCUAUGAUAGCAGUUAUCACCACUGCCGUGAGUAUUCCUUCAAUAAGGGCUGGUAAUAAUGCCUGGAUGCAAUCAUUCUAUGACACAGUUACACAUGCUUUCUGAUCUCAGUAUUUACCAUAAUAAAUCGGCUCCUAUAAUUGAGGCAUACCACCCUCAAAAACCUAUUUGUAAACAGGAUUGGACCCAGUUAGAAAAAAUGAACGUACUUAUUUAGGAAGAUUGCUUUGCAGAAUAGGCAGAGAUGCUGCACAACGAUUCCUAUGGAAUCAUUACUAAUUGGUCCCCCAAGGGGAUGUUUAGCUUGAAUUGCACCUCUCAGUCUGCAUGCCACGGUCACACUAUGUUCAGAUGAUCUGAACAAAACAGUCAGAUGGUAGAAAUGUUAAGUACGGCAAAAGUUCCUAUUAUCUGGAACCAUGGCGGUAUAGUGGCACCUCAACCUCAAAUAAUAUGGCCCGCUCUAGGAGCUAAACAUAAGGAUUUGUAAAAACUAUUAAAUGCUCUUAAUAAGAUCAAAAUUUGGGAAAGAAUAAAAGAGUAUCUAGAAGGACACUCUACAAACUUGUUUUUGGAUAUAGCAAAAUUAAAAGAACAAAUAUGUAAAGCAUCCCGGGCAACCUGACCUUAAUGCCAGGAACCAGAGUGCUUAAAGGAGCUGCAGAAAAAUUAGCAGCUAGUAACCCAUUUAAAUGGGUAAAAACACUUGGAAGCUCUGUGAUUUCAAUGAUGACUAUGCUUUUUAAUCUGUUGUUUGCCUUUGUAUAGUCUGCAGAUGCGGAUCCCGACUCCUGCGAGAGUCUCUUUGCAAAUCGAAGAAGGGAGACAUGUUGGGAGCAAGCCCCCCAGAGUCUGGCCAUAAACUGGCCCCAAAACUGGCCAUAAGCAAAACCUCUGCAGCACUAAAACAUGUCCAUAAUGGCCCUAACGCCCAAUCUGGAAGGUUGUGGGUUUAUGGGAAUGAGAGCAAGGAACACCUGGCCUGCCCAGGGCGGAAAACCGCUUAAAGGCAUUCUUAAGCCACAAACAAAAGCAUGAGCGAUCUGUGUCUUACGGGUGUGUUCCUGCUGCAAUUAAUUCAGCCCAUCCCUUUGUUUCCCAUAAGGGAUACUUUUAGUUAAUUUAAUAUCUAUAGAAACAAUGCUAAUGACUGGUUUGCUGUUAAAUGAAGGGGUGGGUUGCCCCUCCACACCUGUGGGUGUUUCUCGUUAGGUGGAACGAGAGACUUGGAAAAGAGACACAGAGACAAAGUAUAGAGAAAGAAAAGUGGGCCCAGGGGACCAGCAUUCAGCAUACAGAGGAUCCACACUGGCACCGGCCUCUGAGUUCCCUUAGUAUUUAUUGAUCAUUAUCGAGCAUGGCAGGAUAAUAGGAUAAUAGUGGAGAGAAGGUCAGAAGGUAAACACAUGAACAAAGGUCUCUGCAUCAUAAACAAGGUAAAGAAUUAAGUGCUGUGCUUUAGAUAUGUAUACACAUAAACAUCUCAAUGCCUUAAAGAGCAGUAUUGCUGCCCGCAUGUCAUACCUACAGCCCUAAGGCGGUUUUCCCCUAUCUCAGUAGAUGGAAGUAUAUUCCAUGUAAAGUAAAUCGGCUUUACACCCAGACAUUCCAUUGCCCAGAGACGAGCAGGAGACAGAAGCCUUCCUCUUAUCUCAACUGCAAAGAGGUGUUCCUUCCUCUUUUACUAAUCCUCCUCAGCACAGACCCUUUAUGGGUGUCGGGCUGGGGGAUGGUCAGGUCUUUCCCUUCCCACGAGGCCAUAUUUCAGACUAUCACAUGGGGAGAAACCUUGGACAAUACCUGGCUUUCCUAGGCAGAGGUCCCUGCGGCCUUUGCAGUAUUUUGCGUCUCUGGGUACUUGAGAUUAGGGAGUGGUUUGAGAUUAGGGAGUGGUGAUGACUCUUAAGGAGCAUGCUGCCUUCAAGCAUUUGUUUAACAAAGCACAUCUUGCACAGCCCUUAAUCCAUUUAACCCUGAGUUGACACAGCACAUGUUUCAGGGAGCACAGGGUUGGGGGUAAGGUUACAGAUUAACGGCAUCUCAAGGCAGAAGAAUUUUUCUUAAUACAGAACAAAAUGGAGUCUCCUAUGUCUACUUCUUUCUACACAGACACAGUAACAAUCUGAUCUCUCUUUUCCCCACAGUUAAUAAAUAUGUGGGUAAAUCUCUGUUGGGGGCUCUCAGCUCUGAAGGCUGUGAGACCCCUGAUUUUCUACUUCACACCUCUAUAUUUUUGUGUGUGUGUCUUUAAUUCCUCUAGCGCUGCUGAGUUAGUGACCGAGCUGGUCUCGGCAGAGGUGGGCGGGUCUUUUGAGUUCAGGAGUUCAAGAGCAGCCUGGCCAACAUGGUGAAACCCCUUCUCUACUAAAAAUAUGAAAAUUAUCCGGGCAUGGUGGUGUGCCUCUGUACUUUCAGCUACUCAGGAAGCUGAGGCACAAGAAUUGCUGGAACAUGGGAGGUGGAGGCUGCAGUGAGCUGAGAUCAUGCCACUGCACUCCAGCCCAGGCAAUAGAGUAAGACUCUGUCUCAAAACAAAAAGAGUUUUAGGCCAGGUGUGGUGGCUCACGCCUGUAAUCCCAGCACUUUGGGAGGCUGAGGUGGGCAGAUCACCUGAGGUCAGGAGUUCGAGACCAGUCUGGCCAACAUGGCGAAACCCCAUCUCUCUCUACUAAAAAUACAAAAUUUAGCCAGGUGUGGUGGUGGGUGCCUGUAAUCACAGCUGCUUGGGAGGCUGAGGCAGGAGAAUUGGUUGAACCCAGGAGGCAGAGGUUACAGUGAGCAGAGAUCGUGCCACUGCAUUCCAGCCGGGGUAAGAGAGCGAGACUCUGCCUCAAAAAAAGAAGGCUUAGUGUGCAACUCAUCAGAGUUGCACAGGGCAGAGAAAGAAUGGGAAAAAAACAAUUUCUAGAAAACUUUUCGAAUUUUCUGAUCAACACCAAAUAUUCCAAAUAGGAAAAAUACAAAAAAAUCCAUACCUAUAUGUGGCAUAAUAUGAUUGUAGAGCACCAAAGUAAAAGAUCUUAUUUUUUAUUAAAAUUAAAAAAAAAUUAAAAUAGAGGGUCUCACUAUGCUGCCCAGGCUGGUCUUGAACUCCUGGCUUCAAGCUAUCCUCCCACCAUGGCAUCCUAAAGUGCUGGGAUUGCAGGCAUGAGCUGCUGCAUCUGGCCCAAAGUAAAAGAUCUUAGAAGCGGCCAGAAAAAAUAGAUUUGGGCUGGGCAUGAAUAGAUUGAUCACCAAAAAGGUGGCAGACUAACUUCUCGACAGAAUCCACAGAAGCCAGAAGGCAGUGGAACAUUAGCUUUGAUGUACUAAAAUAAAAUACCACGCUAGGCUCCUACAUACAGUGAAAAUGUUUUGAGAAUGAGAAUUAUAAUUUUUUGGCAAACAAAACUAAAGGAGUUUACAACUAAGAAACUCUUUUGUGAGACAGCCUUGCUCUGUUGCCCAGGCUGGAGUGCAGUGACGAAAUCUCAGCUCACUGCAACCUCGGCCUCCCGGGUUCAGGCAAUUCUUGUGUCUCAGCCUUCCAAGUAGCUGGGAUUACAGAUGUGCGCCACCAGGCCCAGCUACUUUUUAUAUUUUUAGUGGAGAUGGGGUUUCACUGUGUUGGCCAGGCUGGUCUCAAACUCCUGACUUCAAGUGAUCUGCCCGCCUUGGCCUGCUAAAGUGCUGGGAUUACAGGCAUGAGCGACUGUGCCUCUCCAGUCCCUGUGUUUUUUUUUGUUUUUGGAGGUUUUAUUUGUUUGUUUUUAGAGACACUUUCACUGUGUUGCCCAGGCCUGUCUGUUGGCCUCAAGUGAUCCUCCUGCCUUGGAUCUCCCAAAGUGCUGGGAUUACAGGUGUGAACCACUGUGCUCAGCCCAUUUUUUAUUUGUUUCUUGAAGGAAGGUAGCAGUAUUAAUUAAUUUUGGACUUUGCUCACUAAAGUUUGAAUGUUAAGAAUAGAUGUAUACAGUCUGGAUGCAGUGGUGCAUGCUUGUAAUUUUAGCACUUUGGGAGGCUGAAGCGGGAGGAUCGCUUGGGCUCAAGAGUUUGAGACCAGCCUGGGCAACAUGGUGAAACCUUGUCUCUACAAAAAAAUUUUAAAAAAUUAGCCAGACAUGAUGGCAUGCACCUAUAAUCCCAGCUACUUGGGAGGCUGAGGUGGGAGGAUUGCUUGAGUCCAGGGAGGUCGAGGCUGCAGUGAGCCAUGAUCACACCACUGCACUCCAGCCUGGGUGACAGAGUGAUACUGUCUC